AGUUGUACGUUCGAAACCUGUCGCCGUCACUUGCGCGUUUGGCAUUAUCCAUUGUCACCGCGGAGGAACGAGCGCUCGAGAUAUCAUCAGUGCCCGCAAAUCUCCGCGCCAAGGCGCUGAGCUACUCCUUUCCGAGGUGCGCCUCUGGUCCUCCGUCCCUGGUGCCCAGCAGCGGCGAGGCGGCAUCUCCGCUCCCGCCGCCGUGUCCACCGAGCCCUGGGAUCAGGGUGGCAGUUCUCAACGAUGGGCAGGAGGGACCUCGGCGGCGACCCCUAAAACAAUACCAUGCCCCGGGAUCCCCGCUGCUGCCGCGCCAGCGUCUUCCCUUUCCACCUCCCUGACCCUGUCGGAUUCGGAUGAGCCCAUUGCAAGGAGAAGACGCAGCCGUCAGAGCGCCUGCGGAGGUGGCGAAGGCUUGGAGAGCAUACGAGGCGGAAUCCGGAUCGAGUGAGUUCCUUGAGCCGCUUGCGUGGGACGCAGGGAGAGGGCGAAUAACGCCCUCAGGCGCUGAAUGCAGGGGCAAGGAGCCAGCGAGGGUGGCUGGAGCAGGCCUUGCCAGCUGUUACCAAGUCUCUCCACAGGCUUGGGGGCUUGGGGCCUCCUGGAAAGAUCCCUCCGCCGCGCUGACCAGUACGGGGCUCGCUCCCGCACUUUGAAGGCUGCCGCGGUCUUUCGUCAUUUAUAAUCAAGCCCAAGAUCAAGGUUGCAAGCUGAGGUCGGGGUACUGACAACGGGAAUGAAGCCAUAGGGGAAGAGGAUAACUGGGACGGGCUGGACCCAUACUUGAUACCCGGGAAACUCCUAGAGCGUGUGGUGCUCCUGCCAGCGGCAGUUACUGGUGGAGCUGAGGCCACCGCUACUGUCGUCGUUGGCGCUUUGCUUCUGGAACCUCCCAGCAAGAUGGCACUCACUGUCUGUUCCCUUCCGAUUAGCACCCCCAGCCGCGCUCCCUCCUCCCCGGGAUACGUAUUAGUCACAUACUGUGGGGAGAAGAUGGGCUAUGUAAAUAUUGCAGAUUGAGCUUAACCAAGAAGUUCGUAGGCUAAUCAAGGCUGGCUUGACCUACAAAAGAAGAAGAGAGUUCUGCCUGCCCACUUGGGCUUGUGUUGACACGGCUGAUAACUUGCCAUCACCUGUUGCCAGUGUGGAAAAAUUCUCCCUGUUGAAUUUUUUGCACAUGGAGGACAGCAGCAAAGAGGGCAACACAGGCUGAUAAGACCAGAGACAGCAGGGAGAUUAUUUUACCAUACGCCCUCAGGACGUUCCCUCUAGCUGGAGUUCUGGACUUCAACAGAACCCCAUCCAGUCAUUUUGAUUUUGCUGUUUAUUUUUUUUUUCUUUUUCUUUUUCCCACCACAUUGUAUUUUAUUUCCGUACUUCAGAAAUGGGCCUACAGACCACAAAGUGGCCCAGCCAUGGGGCUUUUUUCCUGAAGUCUUGGCUUAUCAUUUCCCUGGGGCUCUACUCACAGGUGUCCAAACUCCUGGCCUGCCCUAGUGUGUGCCGCUGCGACAGGAACUUUGUCUACUGUAAUGAGCGAAGCUUGACCUCAGUGCCUCUUGGGAUCCCGGAGGGCGUAACUGUACUCUACCUCCACAACAACCAAAUUAAUAAUGCUGGAUUUCCUGCAGAACUGCACAAUGUACAGUCGGUGCACACGGUCUACCUGUAUGGCAACCAACUGGACGAAUUCCCCAUGAACCUUCCCAAGAAUGUCAGAGUUCUCCAUUUGCAGGAAAACAAUAUUCAGACCAUUUCACGGGCUGCUCUUGCCCAGCUCUUGAAGCUUGAAGAGCUGCACCUGGAUGACAACUCCAUAUCCACAGUGGGGGUGGAAGACGGGGCCUUCCGGGAGGCUAUUAGCCUCAAAUUGUUGUUUUUGUCUAAGAAUCACCUGAGCAGUGUGCCUGUUGGGCUUCCUGUGGACUUGCAAGAGCUGAGAGUGGAUGAAAAUCGAAUUGCUGUCAUAUCCGACAUGGCCUUCCAGAAUCUCACGAGCUUGGAGCGUCUUAUUGUGGACGGGAACCUCCUGACCAACAAGGGUAUCGCCGAGGGCACCUUCAGCCAUCUCACCAAGCUCAAGGAAUUUUCAAUUGUACGUAAUUCGCUGUCCCACCCUCCUCCCGAUCUCCCAGGUACGCAUCUGAUCAGGCUCUAUUUGCAGGACAACCAGAUAAACCACAUUCCUUUGACAGCCUUCUCAAAUCUGCGUAAGCUGGAACGGCUGGAUAUAUCCAACAACCAACUGCGGAUGCUGACUCAAGGGGUUUUUGAUAAUCUCUCCAACCUGAAGCAGCUCACUGCUCGGAAUAACCCUUGGUUUUGUGACUGCAGUAUUAAAUGGGUCACAGAAUGGCUCAAAUAUAUCCCUUCAUCUCUCAACGUGCGGGGUUUCAUGUGCCAAGGUCCUGAACAAGUCCGGGGGAUGGCCGUCAGGGAAUUAAAUAUGAAUCUUUUGUCCUGUCCCACCACGACCCCCGGCCUGCCUCUCUUCACCCCAGCCCCAAGUACAGCUUCUCCGACCACUCAGCCUCCCACCCUCUCUAUUCCAAACCCUAGCAGAAGCUACACGCCUCCAACUCCUACCACAUCGAAACUUCCCACGAUUCCUGACUGGGAUGGCAGAGAAAGAGUGACCCCACCUAUUUCUGAACGGAUCCAGCUCUCUAUCCAUUUUGUGAAUGAUACUUCCAUUCAAGUCAGCUGGCUCUCUCUCUUCACCGUGAUGGCAUACAAACUCACAUGGGUGAAAAUGGGCCACAGUUUAGUAGGGGGCAUCGUUCAGGAGCGCAUAGUCAGCGGUGAGAAGCAACACCUGAGCCUGGUUAACUUAGAGCCCCGAUCCACCUAUCGGAUUUGUUUAGUGCCACUGGAUGCUUUUAACUACCGCGCGGUAGAAGACACCAUUUGUUCAGAGGCCACCACCCAUGCCUCCUAUCUGAACAACGGCAGCAACACAGCGUCCAGCCAUGAGCAGACGACGUCCCACAGCAUGGGCUCCCCCUUUCUGCUGGCGGGCUUGAUCGGGGGCGCGGUGAUAUUUGUGCUGGUGGUCUUGCUCAGCGUCUUUUGCUGGCAUAUGCACAAAAAGGGGCGCUACACCUCCCAGAAGUGGAAAUACAACCGGGGCCGGCGGAAAGAUGAUUAUUGCGAGGCAGGCACCAAGAAGGACAACUCCAUCCUGGAGAUGACAGAAACCAGUUUUCAGAUCGUCUCCUUAAAUAACGAUCAACUCCUUAAAGGAGAUUUCAGACUGCAGCCCAUUUACACCCCAAAUGGGGGCAUUAAUUACACAGACUGCCAUAUCCCCAACAACAUGCGAUACUGCAACAGCAGCGUGCCAGACCUGGAGCACUGCCAUACGUGACAGCCAGAGGCCCAGCGUUAUCAAGGCGGACAAUUAGACUCUUGAGAACACACUCGUGUGUGCACAUAAAGACACGCAGAUUACAUUUGAUAAAUGUUACACAGAUGCAUUUGUGCAUUUGAAUACUCUGUAAUUUAUACGGUGUACUAUAUAAUGGGAUUUAAAAAAAGUGCUAUCUUUUCUAUUUCAAGUUAAUUACAAACAGUUUUGUAACUCUUUGCUUUUUAAAUCUUAAAAAAAAAAAAGUUGCUGAAGUACUGUACAGGGUUGUACAAUGAGAACCCAAUGCCAAGGCAAAAAGAACGAGUGAUUUUUCCUUAGGAUACACAUCAACCACUUUGCUGUUGAAGCUGUCAGAAUAAAUUCCUGGUGGUCAGAUGAAAGGGCAGAUUAAAUGGACUCAUCAGGGUAAGAGGAAUAAUAUGGGUAAAACAAGAAAUGGCCCGAUAGUUUCACACUAUUCCUAUACCUCCAGGUCCGGAAGACAGGUAAAAAAUUCUAUAAUGUAAGAAUGGAGGUAGUUACCCUGAUUUGACCCUGUGUGGGAAAUGCUGAAAGCACCAGGAGGAAGCCGGUUCCCGUGAGAUAAGUUAACCCGGCCUGACAGAAUCAAGAAAAUUGAGAUGAGAUUUGAAAGGACCCGAAAAUGCAGGGGUUGGCUUUCUGACUGGGAACUUAAAAAUCACUCUUCAUGCUUCCCUGGUCCUAUGUGAUAACAGAGUUAGAGACUUGAGUCUGAUUUCAGUCAUCUUCAGGGACCAGUCUGAUGUUGUAGCAAGAAGACUCCCUUUAAAAGUGUUACUGUUCAAAUCAUAUAUCAGGUUGAAUCACAUUCAACAGAGAUAUAUUCUAGAAUACUUUUUUAGAAGAGGCUAAUAAAGGGAAGAAUUAUAUUGAAUGGAAUUAUUUUUGAUAAUGAGAAUUAUUUGGGUAGAUUCACUGAGGCUAUGUCAACAUGAUAUUUAGACCAACAGGUGAUCAAUGUUUGGAAAAUACAACAAUGACUUAUUUAAAAAUUACCCUUCCUGCUAUUUAGACAAAAACAACUGAUCAGUGGUUCUGUUAUGUCAGCUGACUUUGUUAGUAUCAUGUUGAAAUAGCUUGAAGUAAUAUCUUUUAUCCCCUUGCAAAUUCUUGUCUUCCAAUCAUCUCCCAUAUAUUUUCAUAAUUAGUUGUUUAUGACACCUUUGUUUUUCUCCCUCUGUUCAGUAUUUCAAGGAAAAUUAUGGAUGCCAGUCUUGGCUGCACAAGAUAUCCAUUACGUACUUAUACAUUUUAAAAUGAGUACUAAUUUUCACUGCUAAUAAUUCUGUAAGGACACAUCAAAGCUGGCCAAAAUAAUGAAUUUUUUUUAAAAAGCAAUACCUGGUUUCCACCUUGGACUGACUUUGAUCCUGUUCCACUUUUGAAAUUUUAUUUGUUCCUUUUCCAUCGUGGAUGUUCCUCUACUUUGGCAAUUGUGGAGGGCUAAUCAAUCUUAUGUUAGCAGGACAACCCAUGAAAAACAAGUCAGAGAGUGAAGGCUUUUUCCCCUAAUCCUGGCAGAGCAGGGCGUAGAAAAGAGAGGAUGUCCGUGCUUAAUUCUAGAUACUUUUGAGACAACACCUUCAGAAAACACAUAAUUUAAUCUUUGCCAUCCUUAGAUAGAGAAGGGCUAUAGAUCACAUACGUUAUCAAAAACUACUCCCUUGGAAAAAAUAUCUUUCGAAAAUCAAAUUUAAACAUUUCACUCUGUGCUGCAUAUUUCUUUUACCAUUGACCAUUAUUAUAGGGACCCAUGAAGUAAAUGUCACAAUCAUCUUACUAGCUCUCUCUCUCUCAGCAAAAUAAAACUGUGAUGUGUCUUCUUUGUAAAAGUUUAGGUAUAAAAUGCUAUGCAACUUUUUCUUUAUAGUAAGAGCUUUAUUUUCUUUAAUAAUAUAGCCCAACUUAUAUGUUUUAAUCUCCCUUGUCCCUCAGAAUAAGCAGAAAAUAUAACUGCAGCUGUAUGUCGUAGACACAAGAAUUGAAACUGUGCAGUCAGUAGAGCUGAACUUAGCUAUGAAUUAAUUUAAAUUAAUUCUAAAGUGACUCUGGUUUCCAUUUUAGUCUAUUAGCUAGAGGGUUUUGGCUGUUGCUUUUUUUAAAGUUAGGUCCACACAGUGAAGGGAAAAGAGUCUGUGAAGGUGAUCAGUGUAGCAGUAAGACAUCUAAAAUCAAGACAAUGACAUGGGGGCUUUGUGUACUUAGCUGGAUAAUUCCCUUCUACUGUCCUCUUCCCCUUGGCUGUGUAGAUAAAAUUGUGCAUUCAAAUGAUGGUACUUUGACUUUUGAGGGUUUUUAUUUCUGUUAUUCACAAAAUACUCAUUCUCAUUUAUGUAUAUUGUAUGUUUAACCCCCAGUGGGAUUUCUGGCUGCUGAAACCACUUUGGGCCAGGAAGAACAAGGAUGAAGAGGUUCCUGUCAUUUCUUAUGGGGUUCACAGAAUUAUUUGGGGCUUAAAUGGUACAAUGGAGACAGUCAUGUGCAAUGCUUAAGAUGGUCUGACAGGGUCCCUUUUGCUGGAGGUGUUCCUGAAGAGAUUGAACCUAGUAACAGGCUUUAUUUUCACCUUGUGUACAACAUGGCAAAGACUGCUAAGAUUAAAAUCCGUCUCCCAUUUGUUACAGCCUCACCUGCACCAGGAUAGAAAGCACGUGAUGGAAUCUGUGAUGUCUAAUGUGUCUUAUGAAAAUUGCCAAACAACUGUCCCUGGGGAUUCUGCUUUGAUUGGCAUUUUUAGUCAUGGGAAUGUAUAUUUGCUGAUAUAUCUGCUCUGUGUUUGGGCCUCUCUUGCUGUCAUUAUGAUGUAUUUUGAGAUGAUUAGUCAAGAGUCAAGGUUGCGAGUACAGGCCAAGACCAUGGGAAAAAAAGCCAUGCUCACUGGCCAAUAAAGAGCUUGAUGCUGCCUGGCCAAAUGAGGUGACUCAGAUAGAAUCUGAUCCCAUUCAGAGCUUGGUAAAUGUCACUGUACAGAAGACAUUGAAAAGGAAGAGGCAUAGUCAUGAUCAAAAGGAUAUAUUGACAGUUAUCUAUAGCCAGGGUAGUUGUUAAUACCUGCUUGUUUGGGGAGAUAUGUUUGAUUAUAGAGAGACUCUGGGCCACCCUCAAACACCGUCAGAUGCAUUAGCAGCCCACUGCAUGGGACAAUCGCAGGCAGAUACGAGGAAUGUAUCCCCUGCCUAUUUUCCUUGUGUAACAAAUGGAAAACAUUCUCCCCUGUGAGAAAUAAUGCAAUUUCUAAUUAUCUGGAUGUUCGUUGAAAAUAUAUUAGACAUUCUCCCUGAGGUUAAAAACAAAAAGUACGUGACCAGUCUGGUAAGAAGUAUUAAUGAAGUAGCUAAUAUUACAGCUUCAUUUUCUACUAGCACCUAUCAUAAUGGUCUUAGUCAUUUCACACAAAUCAGAACUUCCUUCCCCACCAGGGAGGACAACAUCUUCAUGCUGUGAUUGAAGCAUCCAUUCAGAACACGAGGCAAUAUUGCAGUCCACAGGGAAUGGAUGCUUCACUUGAUCUCCGGACCUUGGCUGCAGAGGCCAUCGCAGCUUUUGAAAAGUGAAGGGGUUAAUUCCCAUUGGUGUCUUUGCUUAUAGCAUUUUUCUCUAACCUAUAACAAGGAGACAUUACAUUUUACUUUAGAACAUGAGAAUAGCAGUUUUGCUCAUGACUUACCAUUCCAGCUGCAUGGGAAAGCAAAGCAGAAAACAGUGCCCCAAAUGGAAAAAAGAUACUCACACAGAACAAAACAGUUCUUGGUCUUGUUCUUGGUCUUGUCAAACCUUGCCUGAUGCUCUUUCUAAAGUCAAAAUAUGAAUGCUAAGAAGGCAUAACCUACAUCCUUCUCUGAUUUCUUCAGCAGGGUCAAAAGACAGUUACUAGCAAUGGGGAAUGCUUGUCACUGUGGAGAAAGAGUUUUGUAUAUGUCUGAUACCGUUGUUAUAACAAAACAAAUUUUUUUACUAUAGUUUUUUGUUUUCUACCUGCACACCCACCAGAAGAGCACAAAGCAAGGCCAUUGCAACAGGCAUUUAAAAAUUAUUAUCAAACAUGCACAUGCUUGUACACACACACACACACACACACAAACAGGGGCAUUUGUAAAGGUGUCCCUGGAAUGUAAGAUUUAUAAUGUUUAAGGCAAGGUGAAGGCAUUGCCAAGUGUGUGUCGCUCAUAGGACUAGUGUAUAUUCACUGAAAGUUAACCUGAUGAUUUGUUAUUGUUUGAACCAUAUGCUGAUUUGCUUCUGGUUUCUGUUUAGUGUGUUCUCUCUGAUAAGGGGCUGAAAGAUUCUGCAUCACACAUCCUCUGAGACCUACCAUGUCGCACACUUUGUUAAUGACAAACUUCACUCUACACUAUACAGUACCUUGUUGAUAUAUUCAGUAAAGUCUUAUUUUAAAAGAAAACCACAUUGUGUUUAUCUGAGUAAGUUCAUUGGGAUACAGUCAAUACUUGUGCUGUUAAUGUAGAAGAAAUGACGCAGGAGGGCAGGAAUAAAAGAGGUAAUAGGACUUUCGUAUUCUCCUAUCAUGAAUAUGACUUGCAUUUCUAAAGGCCAUUUGAUCCUUUUUGUGUGAGGAGUUUAUAUGAAAUCCUCAUGUUCUUUUAAAUUUCCCAACUAAAUUGUGUGUUCCUACGAAUACCUUUUAGGUAUGCACACAUACACAGAGCAUCUUAUUUUAUACUGGUGAAAUCUAUGUUGUUUAGGAUACAGAUAAUGUCAUUGUAUUUAUCCUAUCAGAAUAGGCUUUUCCCCUAUUUCAAAAUAGAUGCUAUUGGCUUUAUUUUUUAUUUUUAAAUUUUUUUUAAACACGGUCUUACCAUGUUGCCCAGGCUGGUCUCAAACUCCUAGAUGCAAGCAAUCAUCCCACCUCGAUCACCCAAAGUGCUGGGAGUACAGGCAGAGGACACCAUGCCCAGCCACGCUAUUGGUUUUAAAUGUCAGAUUUCUUUAAGAAUUCUCAUAGUACUUUUCUGCCGCAGAAUUUAUAGCACAUCUGUCCAUCCUUUCAAUAGGCACUCAAGGAAAUGUAUCUAUUCAUAUGCUCAACUUCAAUUGAUUAGUCUCAUAUGAUUUUUCAGAACCCCUUUUGCUAACCCCUCUUGGCCAUUUCAUUAAUAAUGUAUUUGACAGAGAUUGAAUCAGGAAAUAAAUUCAUGACAUUUCAGUUAACUAGUAUUACCUGUUUGUAGAAUCUCUGUUGGAACAUUGACUAUGAAAGACAGUGCUAACAAGUAAUUCAUAUUACUUUUGGGGAUUUUAUGUAAAGUAACAUCUAUGCUAUUCUUGGGUACUUUUGCCAAGAGUUACAGACCUUAUUCUAUACAGACUAAACCAUUAGUCAAAAAAUACCAUUCAUUCAAAAUAAUUCAUUAAUGUCCUCCUACUCUGUUCCAAACACUAGGCUGAGUUCAGAGGCCUCACAGAAUAGUGAAAUGCGUUCUUAGCCAAAUCAGGCAAAUCUUCUCCCUCACUAUGUCCCUGAAGAAAUCUCUUCAUCUGAUAUAUUUACUAUUCAUCUACUUUCUACAGCACUAUGUUAGGGUCUUCCGGGGAUUCAGAGAAAAGUGUCUGUGAGCCAUUAAGAAACUCACAGAUCAGGUAAUAAACACUUUUUCUAAUGCAUUCCAGUGUCUCAGAGCCUGCAUAAUCACUUUAUACUACUUCAUUAAAUUGACAGGACAUCUAAGGUGACAAAAGAGAUGUUUCUACCUGUUGGUAAGGUUGAUGCAACUGUCAUAAUUAGAUGUUCUUGGUUUUUAAUAGAUGCAGCAAUGAGAGAGUACAUUGCUAAAGUCAGAACUUAAUUUGAAUUAAAUUUUCAAGUUUCCACCAAGUAUUUGAAAACUUAGAAAUUGUAUUUCGUAAUUACACAUGCAGACAUUUAAAUUUUUAUUAAGCACCACGAUGGAACUCAAUCUAAAGGAAUAAUGGCACCUGAUAAUUACUAACAACCUUUGUUUAUAUAAGACCUUGUGCAAACUGUGUGAUAACGUAUGUUUGCAUUCUGUCUUUAAAAUAACCCUGUAAGGUGCGUUAUUUUAAUUUUUAGAUUUUAAAACUUAGCUUCAAGAGAAAUUAAGUGAUUAGUCUAUAGCUACAAAUCCUGUAAAUGGCAGAGUCAGGAAUUACCACUGAGCAUGACUCCAUGGACUCUUAAUUGUUUUCCUGCCUCUUAAUAAAUUGACCAUCCUUGAGACUGACUAGCCUUCAGAUUUUUCAUGAUGGAGCUAUCAUAACUUCUCAGUGGAUACAUAUAUUAUCAUUUAUGGCAAAUAAAGGGAACAUUUUAGAAGCCUCAAAAUUCUUGUCUUUUAAAGCCCUUGGUCAUCCAUUCCUAUUUUUUAUAAAAAUUCUUUUUGUGAUUAUUUGAUGGCUGCACAUUUAUCUGAUUUGAAGGUUUCAGAUGGAAUCAAGAUAUGUCUGUACCCAUAGGGUGAGCUGAAAGAGCUACUAAAAGGUCUUCAGUUGGGUUAUUUUUAGGAAUGAAUUUGUUUCGUACUUGAGAUGUUGCUCUAAGUAUUUUGUAGAUUCCGCUGAAAAAGCACGUAUGUCACAAUCUAUUAGGGCAUUAGUAAACUGGCUUCUGAAUUUAUGCUCUUUUUUUUUCCCAUAACAUAGAUAAAAAUGUGUGCUUUAGGGGAUAUUAUAUAAGCUUUAUUUUCACUGGCUCUACUGAAAGUUAAGGAUACAAAAGUUUUUAAUGGUAAUAACCCAAACUAUAUGUCAUUUUAGCACACACAUACCAAUGGGUGAUCAUAUCUGUCUUUUUUUUUUUUUUUUUUUUUUGGUAUGAAGUCUAAACUAGACGAAAACCUCAAUAUAUCCUUAGGGGAAUUCUUAUUACUUCAAUGACAUAAUAAACCUCAGUAUUGGGUCACUCUUUUCCUAAUAUAAAAAACUAUGCUGGCUCAAAAAGUCUUCUAAACUCCCUAGUUGGGAUAGGAUGGGCCUUUGUUGGUUUAGUUUUGAUUUCAUUCAGCAAAUAUUUACCGAGGCCUGGUAAGUUCUGGUGCAGAAUAAGAAUGUUUUCCAGGAGAGUUAAAUUUUGCUCAUCAAAAAUCUUUCUUGGAAGCUGCUGGUUUUUAACCGUCAGCCUGGGCUCUUUCUGCCUCUUUGCUUUUUUUGAGCAGAAUAUGGCCAGGCUGGUCUCAAACUCCUGAUCUUAGGUGAUCCACCCACCUAGGCCUCCCAAAGUGCUGGGAUUACAGGCAUGAGCCACACCACUGCAUUUAAAUAAUCAGCCUAGGAUUCUGCUAGUUCCAGCACCAGAGUGGCCUCUCAAAUGUGUUUUCUCCUCUUGGUUCCCUGACUCUGACUUGGUUAAGACCCUUCCUUUAGUCUUUUUCUAAUUUAGCCUUUCCAACACAUUGAAGGACAAAGGGUAAUCAUAAUCUAUAAGGAAUGCCUGAGUACGAUACUGCAGUGCUUGCAAAACAUGCGUUUUUAUUGCUUGCAAGAUAGAAUUCAAACUCUUUGUGUGACUUAUGUAUCCUACUACAUGUUGCUCCCUGACAUUUCUUACCAAUAUUGCCUCCUCCUUCAUUACAUGCUCUAGAUUAUAUAUAUAUAAUUACAUAUAUAAUCUAGAUUUUAUAUAUAUAUAUAUAUGAAAUGAGCAAACAAAAUGCUUUCAGUUUAUCUUCCUGGGAUCUCAAGUUCCUUCAAACCACUAUAUAUGUGCUCAAGGUCUUUCAUCCUGUGACAUUCCCCUUUGCCUGAUGACAUAUUUGUCCUUUAAGAUACAAGUCAAAGACCUCUCUUCCAAAGCCGCUGGAAUCACACCUGCCAAUUAUCUGACCGCUUUGUGCGGUUAAUAUAACUUUAAAAUACAUUUAUUUUUAGCACCUAUAUAUUGUAAUUUUUUGUGAGUCUGCUUCAUGCCUAUACAAUGGGGCCCCUGGAAACAGAAAACAUAUUCUGUAAAUUGUUGUACCUCAUCCAGUGUUAAGAGCCAUGCCCAGGCCCUGGUGGGUGCCCAGCUACAGGGGAAGAGCCACUCUGUCAGUUGCUUAUGGCCAGAUGGCUCUUUUUUUAAUAGCCCCAGAAAGAGCUGUGGAGUUCUGACUUGUGCAAAAUUAGCCUUGCUCAAAGACCACAGUAUGCGUUUUACAAGAACAAACAAACAUAUAUAUUUUCCUUAAAAUCUCUUGAUUACUCAUCAACAUUUUUAAAAGAAAUUUUGUUUUUAUGAUUAUUUGGUGGCCAUGCAUCUGAUUUGAAAGCUUUAGAUGGAAUCAGUAUGUCUACAUUCAUAGGAUGUGCUGAGAUAACAAUUAAAAAGACCUGAAGAACAUCUUUUUAUUUUAUUUAUUUAUUUUUUUUUGAGUUGGAGUCUCACUCUGUCACCAGAUUGGAGUGCAGUGGCACAAGCUCGGCUCACUGCAACCUCCGCCUCCCGGGUUCAAGCAAUUCUCCUGCCUCAGCCUCCUGCGUAGCUGGGACUACAGGCGUGCACCACCAUGCCUGGCUAAUUUUUUGUAUUUUUAGUAGAGAUGGGUUUUGCCACAUUGGCCAGGCUAGUCUCGAACUCCUGACCUCAGGUGAUCCCCCCACCUAGGCCUCCCAAAGUGCUGGGAUUACAGGUGUGAGCCACUGCGCCCAGCCAAGAACAUCCUUUUUAUAUAUUACAGACAAACUCAAAACUGAACCAGCUUGCAGAAAAGCAUACAAAGAGGUAUCUUUAAAAAUCACCUUAAUCCCAGCACUUUGGGAGGCCGAGGUGGGCAGAUCACGAGGUCAAGAAAUCAAGACCAUCCUGGCCAACAUGGUGAAACCCUGUCUCUACUAAAAAUACAAAAAAUUUAGCCGGGCUUGGUGGUGCGUGCCUGUAGUCCCAGCUACUCAGGAGGCUGAGGCAGGAGAAUUGCUUGAACCUAGGAGGUGGAGGUUGCAGUGAGCCAAGAUCAUGCCAUUGCACUCCAGCCUGGUGACAGAGUGAGACUCAAAAAAAAAAAAAAAAAAAUCACCUUGCAACAAAAUAUCGCCAUCAUGAAAAGUCCACAAAGCACAAGUAGACACAAAGUUAAACAUUUCGACAGUCGGCUAGUCAAAAUGAAUUCUUUGCAUGUGAAAAGCAGAGAUUUUUUUUUUUUCAUCUUCAUCAGCAAAAUUAAAAAAGACAGUCAUUAUUCACUAUGUCAUAUCCCAUAUAAAAAUACAGCAUAUAUCAUUUAAAGGUUCACAUUGUGUUAUCUUGGUUAUUGCCAUGAGAAUAGUCUUUCCUAGAAAUGAUAUGCUUGUAAAGAAGGGAGUGGAGAGUGGUAGUUAUUAAGAAAUCAGUUUGAAAUCAAGCUGACUUACUUUGGAAUCCUGCUUCAACCACUGACCUGCCAAUUUGCCUUGGCAAUAACUUGCACUUUAGGGUUAUCAGUGUACUUUUCCUAAAAUGGGGACAAUGAUGUCUAACACAUAUGGUGGUUGUCAGAAUUAAAGGCAUAUAUAGUAGUUGACAGAGUAUCUGGUACUGAGUAUACAUUGAAUAAAUGACAUGAAGCACCAUGUAUUUUUCAUGCAGAUGUAAUUCACAAGCACAUGGUGACAAAUUGCCAGCUUUUUAUGAUGAAAAUCAAAUUUCUUGUGUAUUGGGGUAAGAAUUACAUGUAGAGAUGAUCUAUUUAAAGGUAAUUAGCAUUCAAAAUUCCUCAAAACACUCAAUAAUUUGCACAGCUAUUAUCAAGAUGGGUCUGUCAGAAAGGUUUUCAUUAUUCUGUAUUCUUUCUGGGGGAAAAAAAUUGGGAAGAUGAGGUGCCAUGGGAUAACACACAACCAUGGCAGGCCUUUUUUCUCAUGGUGUGUGGGAUCAUUGAACAACAUGGUUGAACAGAAAGAGAACAGACUUCUUUAUAAUGUAGCAUAUAUUCUAUCUGGUUGCUAGAGUACACAUAGAUGUAGUUAUUGCUGAAAAUUAAUUCAGAAUAUGUGGGUGUCAAAAGAGCCCCAGGAAUGAGCAUUCAGAAGGCAUUGGAAAUCAAAAUACUAAAAACAAAAUCAAGAUAAGCUGAGCACAGUGGCUCAUGCCUAUAAUCGCAGUACUUUGGGAGGCCAAGGUGGGAGGAUUGCUUGAGGUCAGGAUUUCCAGACCAGCCUGGGCAAUGCAGUGAGACCCUAUCUCUAAAAAAAAAAAAAAAAAUUAGCCAGGAGUGGUGGCAUGUGCCUAUAGUCCCAGCUACUUGGGAGGUUGAAGCAGGAGGGUCACUUGAGCCCAGGAGAUCAAGAUUACAUUGAGCUCUGAUUGUGCCACUGCACUCCAGCUUAGGCAACUGAGCAAGACCCUGUCUCAAAAAAAAAAAAAAAGUAAUAAAUUUCUGAUAUUGUUUCAAAAAUCUAUAAUUUCUAGUAAGACAUAGUUUUAUUUGAUGCUAGUACACCACCAAUUACGGCAUUUAAAUCCACACUGGGUUUGCUGAUAGUGGGGAUGGUAGCAGUCAAAUGGAAGAACAUUUUAAUGUCUCUACAAUGCAGGUGCAAUAGUCUACCACCUGUCAUGUGGUUACUUUUUGCAAUCGAUAUCAUUAUUAAGUUUGGAAGCUGGUUGUUAUUAACAGGCAUGCAUCCUCUUCAGCUGGAUCACGUUGUUUUCUUUCUGUACACUUUGUGGUAGUUAAUAGUCUCAAAGCAAUUCACUCACUACGGUCUGUAUUAGCAUUAUUUUCCUUUCUAUUUAUGUCUUUCCUUGCUUAAUAAAUGCAGAAGUUCAGACAUUUGAUGAGGGGGGAAAUAUACUUUUUCAGUCCUUGACUGCAUGAUUUAAUUGGUUUCAGGACAGUUAUUUGGCAAGUAGUAUCAAUGGGUACUGGCAUUCCUGUGGUCUGCUGCCAAUCUCUAUUCUGUUUGGACUAGUGUCUGUUUUGACUGGUAGGCCUCAGCUAUCCUAUUGCUAAGUAUUUUACAUAACUGCCCUCAUUAGUUGGAAUAUAGCAUGCUUUACUAGUGUAUCUGAAGUAAGGAGGAAGCAGGAAGUGAGCUGUUUUGUAAUGGAGGCCAAUUAUAUCUAACAGCAACUGUGUCUAUAAGACUGUAGCCUAUUGGAUGGGAAGUUAUAUUAUGAAAACAUGAUGAAUCUUUUAAAUUCUGAGUCCAAUGCUGUCUACAUCUAAAUUUAAAUCCUGGCUCAUACUAACCUUGGUCCUUGGGCAUGUAUAUGCUUCAAUUUUCUCAUCUGUACAUGGGUUAAUAACAACACUCACCUCAACAGUAACCAUACUGCACAGUGCCUGACACAUAUAAAGUGCUCAAUAAAUGCCAGCUACUUUCUGAAAAUAUAUGGAAUUAGUGUGCAAAAAGUUGGGCUAUAUAACUCAAAUCUCCUUUGUAUCUUGGAUAAGACCACUUCUCUCUCGGGCUUGUUUCUUAUAGUCAAAAGCGCAGGAAUUUAGUUGAUCUCCCAAGUUACUUUGGACCUUAAAUUCUGUUUUAUGGUUGUUCAUUUUCUAUGUAGUUUAGAUUUGGUUCAUUGGACUGAUUUGUGUUCUGUGUGCUUUUAAAAUUCAGGAAGAUGUGACUAGGAUAGAUAAAGCAAACAUAUAAACACUCAGUUUCAUUGACUUAAGUAUAAAGACUAACAUGUUUCUCAUUAGUUAUAAUAACCUUAAACUUGAUAUGUUAGGGAAGCAACCUGCAUAACCAUUAAAAUCAGGAGCUACAGAAUCACAAAGAACUGUGACUUUGUAUCUGUGUGAUAUUAUUUAAUGUCCCUAAGCCUCAGUUUCCUCAUAUAUGAAAUGAGGUACUAAUACUUUUAAGGAUUUGAUGAGAUAAUUUAUAUCAUCUUCACUUCAGUGGUUGGCAUAUAUUCAAACCCAUUAUGGCUGAAAAAUUACAAAUGAAUAGAAAGAGAAGCAAGUGAAAACAAAACUCAUUAGUUCAACCACUUCUCCCUCAAAACAAGGAAAUACAAACUAUAUUACUAAGUAGACUAUUAAUAAAACACUUUAUUUAAGUCAAAAUUAUCAAAGAUAGAGUGUCGUACAAUAAAAAUUGUAUAAAAAAUUGUUUAUUAAAAUAUUAAAUAUUUUAUGUUUUCAAGCCAUUAUAUAACAGCUAUUAAACCCUAAUAUUUGACAGAGAAAGAAUUAUGAGAAUAGCUAGAAAAUAUUAAAUAAUAAAUGUGGUUUAUUUUUGAUGGAAUAGAACAGAUUUUAACCCUGAUCCCUGCCACUUUUAUCUGAACCUUGAACAAACAUACAAUUAUGGUUUAAAAAAAAGAAAGAUGAAAACUUUUUAGAAUAAUUAGGAAAUUCUUCUUUCCCAGACCUUCAAUACUUUUAUAAAACCACUACUUAGCAGCUAACAAUGAAAUGUUCAUUUCAAAAUGUUUAGUCUUUAAAGCGGUUACCUAAGAAUAUCUGCCAGUGAACACUAGCUUUAUUUCAUCACAUCAUACACCUGAAUGUAAUCAACAUUGCUUUAUUAAAGAUGUUUAUAUAAUUUUUAUAUAAUACACACUUCCAAUAAUUGAUAAUAGUCUAAUGAUUGAUAUUUUAAAUUAAUGGCUUGUAAUUGUGUAAUUGGAAAGUGGUCCUUGGGACUCAGAUUAAGGUAUCAUUACCUGUUCUUUCAUAAGCUGUUAUUUAUGCUUCUCAUUAAUUAGUUCUUUGUUAUGAAAUCUUUAAAAGUUCAUUAAUUCUGUAAAGGGAAUUUAAUAAAAUGCAAGCAGAUUAGUAAAAUAAUUUGUUUUAAAGUUAGUUUUAAAUAUUAUGCUACCUCUAUAAAGGACCAAAAUAGUAUUUUUAAAAGAAUUUAUCAAAGUAACUAUAAUAAAAGUAUUUAAUGGUAUUUGUAUUGCAAACAUUGAAAUUCUACCUGGCAGUUUAAAGAACAUCACUAACAUUGCCUAAAUGUAGGAAAAUCAAAGGUGAAGUCACCUGCAGAAAAAAAAAAAAAAAAAACAAAAAACAUUCUUAUUAAUCUUAACUAAUUUUCUUUAGUGACAGAAAUUCAAACUUCGAGACAUGUUUGAAACAUUUUAUUUCAGUAAAUAUAGCUGUCACUAUGGAAGUAAUUACUCUAAAGGAAAUCUGUUUUAAAAAGCCAGUAUAAACUGAAAAGUAAGCAACAAAACAUCUUCAGGAAAAGAAAAAGAAAGGCAAAUAAAAUGUUUAUAUGAAAUUACGAACAUUCUGGGCCGGGUGUGGUGGCUCAUGCCUGUAAUCCCAGCACUUUUGGAGGCUGAGGUGGGUGAAUUAUUUAUUUGAGGUCAGGAGUUUGAGACUAGCUUGGCCAACAUGGUGAAAGCCCGCCUUUACUAAAAAUACAAAAAUUAGCAGGGUAUGGUGGCAGGCGCCUGUUAUCCCAGCUACUUGGGAGGCUGAGGCAGCAGAAUUGCUUGAACCUGGGAGGCGGAGGUUGCAGUGAGCUGAGAUAGUGCCACUGCAUUCUAGCCUGGGUGACAGAGCGAUACUUCGUCUCCAAAAAAAAAAAAAAAAAAAAAAAAAGAGAGAGACUAACAUUCUAACAGACAAAACAAAAACAAAAAACAAAAAAACACAUUUUACAAAACAAUAAUCUAAGUGGGCAAGUAAAUACUGGUGUGACAUACAUUUUUAGGGAAAAACUAGCAACAUGUUUUGUGGAGAUAAAUGUAAACACAUUUUACACAUACAAAUCUUUUCUGGCAUGGGUACAAAUGUAACUAAUCAAGUGUAAUUUAUAAACUAUAAAAAAUUUUCAUCUAGACAAAGAAGUUAUUAAAAGCAUUAACAAGUAGUUGAAAAUAUUAUCCCUCUAAGUAUUAGAAAGUUAAACUGCAGUAAUUAAAAGUCAUAUAAGAAUCACCAUGGCAUAGACAUGGUAGGAAAAGCAUUAGCUUUGGCGUUCAAAUAUUGACUCAUUCACUUACCAGCUGUGUUCUCCAGUCAAAAAACUUCACCUCUUUAAUGUUUGGUUUCAUAUUUUUUAAAAGGUAUAACAAAAACACCUACCACAGUGUUGGUGUGAAGACUCAUUUAAAGUUACUAGCACAGUGUCUAGUAUAUACAGUUGCUUUGUUACAUUAACUCCAUUCAAUAUUCUUUCUUUCCACAAUCGUCUGUCACUCCCGGUAGAACUAAGUGAUUUUCCAUGCUCCUGCAAUGACAGCAAAUUUCCCCCAGUCUGCUCUUCCAUGAAUAUCUCAGACAGAGAAGGGUGCCUUCUCAUGUGAUCAGGAGUGAUGUAGCUUUGAGGGUGGACCCACCAUUCCUGCCAUAUUCCUUGGGUAGGCUCAUCUAUCACUUGUCUUAAAGGAAGAUUUGAAACAUAAUAGUUUCCUUUGCGCUUCUGUGGAUGUCUCUGAAAAAGCUGGCAGGGCACACACUCUUGCAAAUUUUUCAUGUUGUAAUCACCCACCAGUGGUAAUAAUAGGGUUAAUUAUAUGAACCCAUAUAGUAGUGUCAUUUAAAGGGAAUUUAAAUUCUCUCUUGUCCUUACUCUGCUCCACCAUCCUCCACUGUGCUUGAAAUGCCUAUCAUUAUCCUUAUUCUUUUGAUACCAGGCAUCACUACAAAAUGUAUACACAUUACCUAGAUUUUCAAGAAGUGAAAUGUUUAGUAACCAUUAUGAUGGAAGCUGGGACUAGGUGACUUAUUCUAAAUGUAACAAUUACCGGUAGAGAAUGGGAUAAAGGACAACUGAGUGUGGAUAGAGAAAGGAGAAAUGGAAGAGUUUGGAGCACGGGCCAUUGCGAUGGACAGACGCCACCGCAGAGAGCAAGGUUUACCUGUGUGGUUGGCAUUCUUGGAAGUGCUCUGGUUCUAUUGGCAGAGAUCCUUGCUGUUAGCCUCUUGCCUUUCGCCCAGGCUGAAGACAGAGUGCUUUCCCAUGGUUCUGUCUUUUUCUCCAGGCAACACUUCCUGAUGACUGAUCAAUAUUGGGGUAGGAAGUCUUAGACAUCUUACUCCAGCUCAGAUCAGCUCUGAUGGGCUGCAGGCUCAGUUUAGGCUUCCCUUGAGAUUUCAUCAUGGCUUUACUUCUCCCUCUACCAGUCCUGGUUCUUCAUAGCCUUCCACAGGUGUCAGCUGCAAAAACCCUCCCAAGUAAGCCUCUUGUAUGCUACUCUGUCUCAGAGUCCAUUUCCUUGGGAACCCAACCUGCUACAGCCUACUUCACACUUCUUCUCAAGGCUGUCUUGAAUUCCUCCAACAAUAGACCCGUUAUUAUGUGAAAGUGUGAGGCUGGGCCCAAGGGAUUUCUUUACUUAUUGAGCAGAGCGAAGUAACAUUAAUUUGUGUUAUAACCACUGAAUGUUCUAAUUCCAUGAAUUUAAAUGACGCACCUGAACAUAUAUGAGGCCUAGAUUUUGCUGCAUGUCCGCAAACCUAUUUUGAUCAACCAGUACUGAACUUUUCCCCUUCUCUUAUGAUUGUCAAAUAACCUUGUUAUAUGCUAAAAAUAAAAGAUUAAAAAACAUACAGUGCAAAAAAGCAAACAAAAGUUAGCUAAUAAUCAAUUCUUUGAACGAAGCCCAGUGAAACCAAGUUUAUCAACUCUAUCUGAAAAUAAAAAUGUCCAAGAAAAUGACAAUCAAAACGAUUAGUGCAUUAGGAUAAGUGUCGUCUCUUGUAGAUAGAUAAAAACUAAACUGAAACCAAAAGAAUUUCCAGAGCAGGCAGUCUCUAUUCUGUAACAAGGUUUUCUCAUGAUCCAGUUAUUUUAAGGAUACCUGCAGGAUCCCACAGGUUUUCUCAGGGAUUUGCUGGAAGCUGGGAAAGUGAUGACUCUCAUUCACUGUUGCCCUGUUUCCUUUUCCUUGACAAAUUCAGUUAACCGGAUGGCAAGUUGUUUAUGAGCAUGCCUUCUCGUUAAGUUGACAAAAUCUUGACAGGAGUAAAAGAUAAUCGAAUUCUCUUUGUGAAGUGAUUUAUGGUUUUAAAAUAAGCAGCUUUUCUUGAAAGUAGUUUACCGGGUUGGGCAAAAAGAGGAUGAGUAUUAAAGGUCAUUAGGCAUUCAAGGUACCACAUUUACUUUCUACAAUGCAAGUAGAAGAAGGGGCCCCACCAGUCAUUCUGAGACGUGUUUCCAUUUUCUGCUACUUUUUAGUGAGCCCAAAUGAUGGUAGCAAUGAUUGAUUUAUCUCAAUCUUCUUGUAUAGCUGCUGAAUUUUCUCUCAUGAGUUUGGCUAAAAUUAGAGUGUGUGUUAGUAGAAUUUAUAUUUAUAGACUAUUGAUAUUAUUAUGUGCAUUACCCAUUUUAAAGAUGGAAACACUGAAGCCCCCAGAAAGGACUGGCUAAGCUCUUACAAUAAGUGAUGGAAUGAGCUUUGAAAACACAGGGCUUAGGAUUUCAAAUCAGGCUGUUUUCCCUCACCGCACCAUGGUGCUUCACUAGCAGAAAUUCUUUAUUUUUUUUUUUUUCCUUUUUUUUUUUUUUUGAGACAGUGUCUCGCUCUGUCCCCCAGGCCAGAGUGCAGCGGCGUGAUCUCGACUCACUGCAAGCUCCGCCUUCCGAGUUCACACCAUUCUCCUGCCUCAGUCUCCCGAGUAGCUGGGACUACAGGCUCCUGCCACCACGCCUGGCUAAUAUUUUGUAUUUUUAGUAGAGACGAGGUUUCACCGUGUUAGCCAGGAUGGUCUCGAUUUCCUGACCUCGUGAUCCGCCCGCCUCGGCCUCCCAAAGUGCUGGGAUUACAGGCGUGAGCCACUGCCCCCCACCCACUAGCAGAAAUUCUUAACAGUUAUUGUUAUCUAACUACUUGACUAGUGUAGAUUCUGCUGUGAGCUUGUGGUGGUUCCUUCUGCAGAUAAAGCAAAGGAAAUCUGGAAAUGGCCAACCUGAAUACUUUAUUUCCAAAACUGUAUAUUUUAUCAGGACAGUAAGGCAAUCAGUGGAGUAAUGAUCCUUCCAAACUGCUGACUACAUCUAGAAUCAUGCAAUUAUUAGUUUUUAAUAAAGAUCGUGACCAAGCUUUCCUUGGGAAGUAAACUUUGGUCACCACAAUAUACAUAGCAAGUAUUAAAUAUCUUGAGAGGUUUUCUUUAAUUGUUUAAUUCAUAGGAAAGCCACUGGGAGCCUUCUGGGAGCCAGAAGCAAAUUAGGAGACACAGAAUUAUUUAAUAAUAAUGGUAAUAAUGACUAAGUUCUCUCAUCAAGGUCUGUACCAUGAUUGAACUACUUGCUGCCAUAAAUUUUUUACUAUUGAAUAAAUAUGCUUUGUGAAUAUUCCAUACAUUUGCUAAGUUCUCACUGGUCAGGUUCAGUCUUUGCUAUUAGAGUCGAGCAUCUCUGCAAAGAGAUUUGAGCCCCUUGAGUAGAACAUAGGCCACAUAGUGUGGCAAACACAUCAUUAGAAACUGCCUCCUAUUCACUCUCUUAAUAGCUUGAGAGAAUUGUACACAAACGUUUCUAAAAUACAGAUCCUACCUUAGGCUUUUCGGCUGCACAGCUGAAUCGCCUCUGUGAAAAUCCUGACCUCGCUUUCUUCUGGCCUUUCUUCCCCGUGACCUUGGGCAAGUUGCUUAAACUGUAGCCAUAAUUUCCUCAUAGAUUUGGUAUGAGUUAAAAUGCAUAGAAAGCAUGUACUACAUCUAGUGCAUUUCUCCAUAAUGUGGGUGGCAAUUAUUCUAAUCCCUUCCACAAAGUAUUUAGUCUAUGACUUAUUUCUGCGAAAACCCACGAAAGUGAAAACUAACAAUAGAGAAGCCUUUUAAAAACCUAACAGCCUCCAAAGACUGAAGAAGAGAGCAUGGUGUUUAAUGCCAGGGUGGAAAGCUGUGACAGUCAGCUUUUUCCCUGGAUAUGGCUUAUUGGUAUUCAUUAUUCCCAAUUCCUUCUAUAUGCCUUCCUUUCUGGAUAGAAUCGAUCACAUUUGCUGGACUCCAUUAUGUUUGGAUUCUAUGUAUAAAUUAGGUUCUACCAAUUACAGGCACGUGUGCAGGAUUUUCAAGGUAGAAGUGAAGUGGAAACUCUCUUCUUACUAAUGUCAGUCUUGGGCCCAAGAGGCCAUCAGGCACGGUGCCCAUAAUCAGUGUUUUAGUGUCUGGUCACUAUCUUCAGUGGAGUCAGGUGAUGUGAAUAGCAGCAGGAGAGACCUGAUUUCUGGAUAAGGACUACAGUAGUACGUCCUUGGACGCAACAGUUUAAGAGGUAGUUCCUGAUUUAUUCCCCUCCCCUUUCCAAUUCAUUCCCUGAUUUUGUGCACACCUAAUACUUAUAUUAAAUACCUCUCCUGCUUUGAAUAAAUGGAAUAAUUUCUGUUUCCUGCAUUUUAUCUUGUUGGAUUAAGUAUUUGAUAAUAAAACUGAUUGUGGGUCUACUUACCUAAGGGUAUAAAUUUGAUAUUGGUUACCUAAACUGUCUGAAUUUGAAAGUAGAGACAAUCUUAUUCAUGCAUAAUGGAUCACUGAUAAUUUUUGGCUUGCAAUGAGAAAAAAAAAUCAGCAGCUGAAAUUAUUACCUGAGAUCACCUGGAAUGAAGAGCCUAUUAAAGCCAAGGCUUUGGUGACCAAUGUGAUUGCUUCAGAAUUUUAUGAUGAGAAUGUAAAUAUAAUAAUUGUGAGGUAGGCUGAAGCAUGUAUAGAAAGAAAACAACAAAUUCAGAGUUUUAAAUAACUGGCUCAAGGCAAGUCAGAGGUCCAAGGAGCAUCUAUGAUUAUCUCCGACACUAUUUUAUUUCUUACAGUUUCAAGGUUGCUGUUGACAAAAAAAAAAAAAAAGAAAGAAAGAAAAAAAUGGCACACAGUGUCUGAUCUUGUUUAUUGCUGAAAUAUAAUUUCAGUUGAAUCACACCCUCAUCAGGUCUUCUCUGUGAAAAUUAGGGCAUUGAGUGAGAAAUAUCAGAAACCCAGAGCAUUAUAAUGGGAAUGUUAGGUAGGUUUAAAUUAUUCUGACUAUACUGAACCCCCAAGUCCGAUGAGCCUUCUUUGCCAGUAGAACUCCUUCAUCUCUGUUAUAUAAGGUUGAUUCUGCCUUUGUGGGGAGAACUAACUUACCUGAGGUAACUAAUGUAAAAUAGCUUGUUCUGAUCACCUCACUGCCUCCAAGUCUAGAGUUAGAGCUCGUUCCCAGUGUCUCAGUAGGGCUUAAAUAUGAAGUAUAAACUGGGAAGAAAAGGCUAAAAUAACAACAAAAAAACGGCAAUAGUUUGUUAUUUUUUAUCAGGAGAAAUCUGCGGACUAUGUAUGGCAACAGACUCAAAGGGAGGUACACCAGGUAGGAAAAAUCAUAACCAGAUUGGGCCAUAUUAGCCAAUAUGGGUACAUAUACUAGAGCCUGCAUGCAAUGAGCUUACCCAACCAGCUCAGAGUGAUUAUAAUUGUUUUGCUUUCUGGAUUGGUUGACUGAAAUCUGGACUCAAUGGUGAGUCACACUAAUUGAAGUUGAGAUGGAAGAAAUUCCUUGGCAUAUUGUAGAAUCUGAAAUAUAGGUUGUAUAUUUAUUAGUCAGUUUGGACUGCUGUAACAAAAAUACCAUAGACUGAGUGGCUUAAACAAUAAACAUUUAUUACUUCCAAUUCUUGAGGCUGUGAAGCCCAAGAUCAAGUUGCCUGCAGAUCUGGUGUCUGGUGAUGCUCCUCUUUUUGAGUUGUAAACAACUGCCCUCAGAAGGCUCUCUCCUGUCUCUUUUUAUUAGGUCAUUAUUCUCAACAUGAGGGCUCCACCCUUAUGGAUUAAUUGCCUCCCAAAGGCCUCAUCUUCAAACACUAUUCCACUCGGGGCUAGGAUGUCAACAUAUGAAAUUUAGGGGCACAUAAAUAUACAGUCCAUAACAGGGAGAUAGGAACAUUGGAGUAACCCAUCAUAUGAUUCACUUUAAUGUCUAAAAACAUCUCAUGAGAGAGUUCAGAGGGUAUUUCUUUUUUUUCUUUCUUUCUUUCUUUCUUUCUUUCUUUCUUUCUUUCUUUCUUUCUUUCUUUCUUUCUUUCUUCCUUCCUUCCUUCCUUCCUUUCUUUCCUUUCUCCUUUUUCUUUUUUUUGUUUUGAGACAGGUUCUCUCUCUGUCACCCAGGCAGGAAUGCAGUGGCGUGAUCUCAGCUCACUGCAACCUCCGCCUCCUGGGUUCAAGCGAUUCUCCUGCCUCAGCCUCCUGAGUAGCUGGGACUACAGGCGUGCACCACCACACCUGACUAAUUUUUGUGUUUUUAGUAGAGACGGGGUUUCACCAUAUUAGCCAGGCUGCUCUCAAACUCCUGACCUCAGGUGAUCCACCCGCCUCAGCUUCCCAAAUCGCUGGGUUUACAGGCGUGAGCCAUUGCACCUGGCCAGAGGGUGUUUCUUUAAGGCAUUUAUUAAUGCAUUGAUGAGGACUCUCCUCUUUUAGAUAGAGAUGAAAGUGUAGAUGCUGCCCACAAAAUGUGCUCCCUGUUUAAGUGGGGUUGGUGGAAUCCUGGAGUGACAGAGAACAAACGACAACAUUUAGUCCAGUUGCAGCAGAGUGGUUGUGGUUUUUAUUAUAAGCAUUAAAAGUAUAGUAGUAGGAAACUGUGUUUAACCUGUUUUCAAGAAUGGAUAAUUGCUCAUUAUAGCUUCAUGAAUAAUAUAGAUGUUCAGCCAACUUAAGUUGUACCUGAAUUGUGCAAAUGAAGGAAAGAUGCAGGUUUGGCAAAUUGAAGCCAGACUAAUUAUCACAAUGUAGUAUCAUUAACACUCACACAAUUCCCAGAUUCAAGGUGCAGCAGUGGAUAUUUCUAAGACGUCCUCAUUUAACUUGAUUUUUUUUUUUAAUCUAUGAAGUAGUUGGCUAUGUUUUGGAGAAUAUACAAUUAAUGUAAGUUUACUCAGGUGGUAAUUCCAGUUGCUAUGGUUGUGGAAGAUAUGGUCUCUACUUAAACAAAUUCAACUGAGCUAUGGCAUCUCCAAUGCAACUGUCAAUUUAGAAAUUUCUUUCUUUUUAUCUCAAUAGGCAAAGAACACUAAAGUAGUCUGCUUUCACUUUCAUUAACACGCCCCAUGGAGAUAUCAUGAAUUACUCUCAGGCCCUUGAUUAUCUUAUCAUACCAGAGGAUGUCCCACAGGUCUACAGCUUAAUAACAUCAUGUGACUGAAGUGGAAGAACUGGAAGGAAAAGAUAACCUAGAAACUCAGUAAUUCACAUGCAUUCAAGAAGGUAGAAGAAAAUUCUCACUAAAACUCAGGGACAUGCCACCUUUUGCAAAUUUCUGGGAGUUUAGUCCGGCAUGUCUGGAAAUCCUUUCCAAAGAAACUGGGCCUGUUCUUGAUGGGCUCCCUGGAUGUUUGAAGGCAACAUAUACUAGUUUUAGAUGCGCUGCUUCGAUACUUUGGAUUCAAUACUUAGUAAUCCCUAAAGCUGUGAAUUUGGAGUUUGUUGCUGAGGAAGAGUAGACUCUCUAGCUUUUCCAGGCUGUGGUCCAGGCUGCUGUCUUUGCUACUUGGUUACAAUGAUCCAGCAAAUUCAACGGUGCAUAAAAUGUUUCAGGCAGAUGGUCAUGCAGUUUGUAAAACUUUGCCAAUCUCGUAGGAGAUUAAUAGCGUAGAGCUCUGUGGUUCUGAAGCAAAAUCAUGCUUUCUUUCUUAGAUUAUUAAUCUCCUUGUGAGGGACAGUUCUUGUCUUGCUAAUAGAAAUAGAUGCCGAAAGAGGCUCAACUGUUGGCUAUUGGAUCCCGAGUAGUAAUGCAACUGAACUGUAAUCAUGAGUUUUGAUCAACCAACCAUAAAGUUGAGCUUGGGCAGCAGAACUCCUACAUCAAGUAAAAAGUAUAUAUAUACACACAUAUGUGUGUAUGUAUAUGUAUACCUAUAUAUAUGUAUACAUAUGUAUAUAUGUACACAUGUGUAUAUAUGUAUAUACAUAUAUGUAUACAUGUGUAUAUAUGUAUACAUGUGUAUAUAUGUAUAUACAUAUAUGUAUAUAGAAGUAUAUAUACACAUAUAAAUGUGUGCGUGUAUAUAUAUAUGAUUGGCUGAGUGCUCUAUUUGUUGCUUGAGCAGGUGUUCACCCUCCCACAUAAAUUCAUCCUACUUAAUUGGCACUUUUUCUUCAACCCAUACCUGCUUCUCAGAGAAACUAUAGAGAAGAGGAAACUUCCAAGUGAGCAGGUCUUUGAAUGGUACAUCUAUUUGUUCACUCUGCUUGGAAACAAAGGUUUCACUAAGCAUGGAUACAAUUUGGAUCAUUGGUAAUAAGGAGACUUAGGGAAGAAAUACGUGUUAAGGAUUGUUCAUAAGUGGCAGAACCUAUGAGAAUAUUCAUGCCACAUGUUAUUUCUUUUCAGAAGAUCUUCCUAGUUGAGGAAUCUUUCAGAGAUUCAGUAGAUAAGGUGAUCUAUUAUAUGGAUGUCAAGCUGUCCUUUUCCCCAGCCACCCUCCUCACGUCUUGCUCAAUGACUUCAUGAAUGAAAAGUUUAUGAUAGCAAAGAUGUUGGUAACAUAUGCAUUCAACAACAUAGUUCAUUUGGUAGAGUCAAUACUGAGUACCUAAGAGCCCAAUUCUGAUACUCUCAUAUUGCACUAUUCACUAGGAGGUUCAGCAAUCUAUUUAGUGGCAGGUGGUGACAGUGGAUUUCUUCUCUUAUGGAAAGGACAACUAUCCAUAUUGAAAUAGACAAUUACUCUGUAUAUAGAUUUGCCUGCCUUGUAACCAUGCCUUUGCAUCUGUUUACUUACUUAAUGGGACAUUAUUAUGGUGACCCAUACAACAUCACUUUUAAACAGUGGAUUUAUUUAUGGCACAGAGGUUAAGAAAAUGAACUCAGGCCGGUAAGAGUCACUGUUAUCAUUCACCACAAGUUGCCUGAAGCAACCAGCCUUUAAAAUACUAUAAUGGACUGUGGAAAAAUCAGUUAGAGUGUCACUUGGAUGAAGCUGUAAUUGGAAGUUGAGGACACUGUCAUUCAGAAUAAGAUGUAUGAUCUGAAUUAGUGGCCAAUACCUGGCCCUUUUUGUCUGUAGUUAAAUGUGAUGUGAGGAAAUACCAAAGCUCAUGGUAAUCUCAGAUGUCAUUGGACAGAGAAGCUCACAGACCAAAUUAAGAUGCUGAAGUCAGAUGACUUAUGAAUCAAUUUAAAACAAAUCAUGAGAAGGAAGGGAGGAAAGGAUGAAGUAGGUUUGCAGUCCUCUUAGAAGAAGGUAAAAGUGGGUAGAAUGGACCAUAGUACUUGAAUCUUGAGUUCAGAAUCAGAUAUUCUUCCUCCUUGGCCUCUUCUGUUUCAGGGCUUCUCGAAUUUUUUUUUCUUUUAUUUAUUUUUUGAGAUGGAGUCUUGCUCUACCACCCAGGCUGGAGUGCAGUGGCACAAUCUUGGCUCAAUGCAACCUCCUUCUCCCAGGUUCAAGGAAUUCUCCUGCCUUAGCCUCUCGAGUAGAUGAGAUUGCAGGUGCCCACCACUACACCCAGCUAAUUUUUGUUUUUUUUGGUAGAGAUGGGGUUUCACCAUGUUGGCCAGGCUGGUUCUGCCUCUUGACUUUAUCAUCCUUCCUCUCUGAUGGUAUGGUUAUGUGGACCAGAACUGAAGUUUAAGGAAGGGGCUUAAGAUAUGGAAGUUGCCUGGGACCAACAUACUCUGUCCAAGAGACACAGUGACACAUACAUGCACAGCUGACCAAAGCUAUAGCUUCCCAAUUACUUGAUGAACAGCUAUGAAUGUUGUUUCUUUUUCUUAGACAAAGUGCAUAUCUGCUCAAGAUGGAUGUCACUAAUGUGCAACUGAUCCACAACCUCAUACAAUUUUAGUAUCUCAUAUGCUUCGUGUACAUGUCAUGUAUGAAGGUGCCUGAGGUACCCCAUGUAUAUAUAGCAUGUUAUGAAUGUUAGGCAUAUUUUGGUCUUUCCUUUCUAUCUAUGUUUAGUAUGCACAAGACAUACUUAUUUUACCUUUGCUUAAUAUGCCUUAUAGUUUACUAACUUACUUAACAGAGGAGUUUUGUUUUCUUGUUAUCUGUAGCAGAAUUGAAUGUUGCCCAGCAAUAUAAUAUAUGUAAAUCAUACCAAAUUAUAUGUGUUUAAAACUCAAGGGAUGGAACUGGGAGAGAUAACACUCAUUUUUCACCUACGCAUCACUCACAAUAUUUAGCUCUCCUUCCACAUGAUGUUGGGAUAUGAUGGCUUAGAAGUCUUACUAGUCAAUGGAAGAAUGUUUCUCUUCCAAGAGGACACAACAAUGAUUCAUUUGAACUCUAUGAUUGCCACUGAAUAAUUUGGUCUUUCCAUGCCUAUAAGCAAAGAAGUUACGUGUAUUAACUGGAACAAUUGGUCCUGAUUAUUAAGGAGAGUAAGUUUUUCCUACAAAGAGAUGUAUGUAUGGGACCCAGGGAAUUUUACAGAAACAUCUCUAAGAACUUCCAUGCUUUUUUGUCAAGUUAAAUGGACAACUAUCGCAACCACAUACAGGCAGAACCACUAAGAGUAAAAACCCCUCAGGAAUUAGGAUUCGGGUCACCCUGCUUGGCAGAGCCCUAAUUAGUCACAGUGCUAGGUGAGGUCAAAAGUAAUAUGAAAUAGGAAGAGGAUAAACAGUGUCAUAAACAACUGUGAUCUUAUGGCCAGUUGCAGAGUAAGAAAUUAAUAACUACUCCUGUUCUCUUCUUUGCCUUGUUAUGCAUGUACUGACUUUUUACCUCUUUCUUUUUCCCUACAAUUUUAUAAAAAUGGUGAUACAUUUGUAAUUUGUCCCUCAAAUUACAGACUAUCAGCUUGAAACUAUGAUUGGAAUUGAAGGUUAAAGAAAACCCAGCUAUAGAUUCAGUGACUAACAAAAUUUGGGGACAGUGUAAGCCUCAUUCUAAUUGCAUAAGGAAUAGUUACUGUAUGUUAGGCAGGUGCAUGUUGUUAUUGCUACUUUUUUCAAGUCUAAGUUCUAGGUACAAAGUGUACACUGUACUGGAUUUAGUAUUUGACAUCUAUUUUCACAUCCUUCUAGGAGUCAUCUUGUACUAAAGAAGCUGUAAGCCCACAUGUGCAUUUCCCAGAGUCCCUUGUUGCUAGGGGGCUGAAUGCGAACGAGGUUUCACCAUUAAAUAUACUUAUACAUUUGGAAAGGCAAAAAUGAGGCAGAGGCCAUCUUUGUGUUGCUGGUUUGAUUAGCAAGUUUGCUAAGACAUGAGUGUCAAGGGAAGUUGAGGUGGAGAUGGUGGCUAUAUGGUGCAGCUGUUUUCCUGAUUCCCAGAGAGCAAUCACUCAGAUGUGCUCUUGUACUUAAUACUUCCACUGGCAGUCCCUUUUCUUUCCUCUUUUAGUUCUUCCUAUAAUUUUCUAAGUGUAUAAUUGCCCAUUUUCCCUAAAUACCUAGGUAGGUUUUAUUUCCUAAACUGGACCUCUUACCAAACACAGAUGAGAUGUACUGUCUGCCACCCUAACUGCCCAUAGGACUCCACCAAGGAUGCCAACUCUAAGUGGUCAUUUACCUCUGUGAUUGUGUUUUUAAUGCCUGCCUCCCAUUAAGUUAUAAGAUCCAGGAAUUUAAUAAUUUAUUUUGAUAAGGACUUAACACAAUGCUUGGCACAUAAGAGGAAUUAAAUAACAUUUUUCUGAAUGAAUAGAUUUUAAACCAUGUGUGAGCAGUCACAGAAUUCACUGAUCUAUUAUAAUUUACCAAUUCCUUUGCAUCAUAGCACCCAUGCAAAAUAUUUUGGCUACAGGGAGUGCUCCAAUUUUGAUACUCUCCCUGUCAAUAUGCCUAUUACCCCAAUAUAAUUUAAGAUUGACAGGGAGAGCAUCAGUAUUCUGCAGUCUGAUUGCAGAAGCAUAUAUGUAAAAAUAUACCUUUUAGAAAUGAUUUUAGAAUCUGGAAAUUUACAAACUAUUAAUUUUCUUUUCUACAGUUUCCUCCAGAAAGCCCCUAUGUAUUUAUUCCGGUUAACAAUUUUACUUGAGUAGAAAUCACUUGACUCAAAUUUUGAUGAUUUAAUAGCUCAUUGAAAGAACUAGCCUGAAGCAGAUAAAAUAUGUUGCAGAUGCUGUAACUCUUAUUUGCAUCCAUUGGUCUUUUGGUUUAUGUGCUUUAAUAAUUUGAAAAACAAGAAGAUAAUCAGGAACCAAGAUGGAUAUGUGUGUCUUGAGGCAGAACUUAAUUCAAAAUUGUUCAGUGUUUUGUCAGAUGAACUCCUUAACCACAUUUGUUAUCAGUAGCACACAAUAUAUUGGAUUAAGUUUUUGAAUGAUGUGCAAAGAUGAUGCCAGAUUGAUCCUAACAAACAUAAAGCUCAGAAUCAAAACCAGAAUGUUGUUUUGAUCAUACUGGUUUUAGGCAAAGGAUUUUAAGAUAAAUUCUUUCAUACUGGAAUUUGUGAUACUAUCCACACUUUUCCUCACUAUAAAAUUUAAUGAACCUUAUAUCAUUAAUAUUUUUGUGUCAAUGGUGAGUUCUUCUUUUUUCUUUACCUGAGUUGUAUCAACAGUUUCAAAGGAGAGAGAGUGUUUUUGGUAAAGGCAAUAAAUUAUUUUUUAAUGUACAUCUUAUACACAUAAAAUACUUUCUCAUAUUCUGAAGAAUGAAGCAUUUCUGUCCUAGGUGAUUAUAAAGUUUGUUGCUAUAGUAUUUCAUUAUUUUUUAUUAGAAAAUAUUUUAAUAACACAAGAAAGUAAAGAAAGUAAUACAAGGAACACUCAUGUACACAUCAACCAGCUUUGUCUGAAAUUAAUAUCAUCCUAAAUUUGCUUCAUUGCUUUUAUUCAUUAAAAAUUACAAAUACAAUUGAAGCCCUUGAACCCCUCACCUGUCACACUAUCCUCUUUGCUUUGUCAAAUACUUACUACGUUCAUAUGUAUUGAUGUACAGUAUAGCCUUAUUUUACGUGUUUUAAAUUUAUACAUAAACAAUUUCAAACUCUAUGAAUCAUUCUACAUUUUGCUAUUUUGUGUUCAAUAUCCUGUUGUCGAAACAUUUCCAUGUUCCUUUAAUUCAUUCAUUGGCAAUACAGUAUAAUAUGUUAUUGUAUAGAUACAUAUAUAUUUAAAAUAUAUAGGUAUUUUAAUUUUACUGUAUUAUAUUGUUGAACAUUUCCACUGUUUUACAUUUUUUAGUAUCAUAAACUAUCCUUCAAUGAACACUCUUUUAAUGUCAUCUGGUGUCAGGUAUGAGAGUUCCUAAACACACACAGUGUAUCUAGAAUUUGAAUUGCUAAAAUUGAACAUUCAAUUUUCAUUUUUAACUUUACUAAAUACUGUAAAAUUGUUCUCUGUGUGCCAAUUUUCUUUACCACUGGUAAAAUGUGAGUUUCCACUUUCACAUGCUUGCCAUUUCCUAUUGCAAAACAUUUAAGUAUUUAUGUUUGUGAUAAAAAUGGAGUCUUAUUUUGAUUUUAAUUUGUACUUCCCCAGUUCCUGUUGUGUUUAAGUUUGUUUUUUAUUUAUUUAUUAUCUGUUCAUGAUUUUCUUCAUUUUUUCUCUUACUGGUUCAUAUUCUCUAUACAUGCUGAAUGGUGUUAGCUAGCUAUAUUCUUUGCAAUAAUUAUUAAAAUUUUCUUUUUCUUUUCUUUUUUUAAGAGACAAGGUCUUACCCUGUCAUCCAGGCUAGGAUGCAGUAGCACGAUCUUAGCUUACUGUAGACUCCAACUCCUGGGCUCAAGAGAUACUCUCCUGCCUUGGUUUCCUAAAGUGCUGGGAUUAUAGGCCUGAGCCACUGGCCUGUUUUGUUUUUCUUAAUAUAAGGCUAUACAUUUCCCUCUAAGAACUAAUUUAGCUGCCUCCCUCAAUCUUUUAUAUGUAAUUUUAAGUUAAUAUUCAGCUUUAAACUUUUCUAAUUCAAUUAUCUUUUUUGAUUAAUCAAUUGUUUAGGAUAAUGUCUCAAAACUUUUUUGGUAUAUAGAUAUCUUUAAUUACAUAUUUCUAAAUUAUUUUCAUUUAAGUCAAAGGACAUAGCCUGGAAAGUAUUCGUUUGUUUGUGUGUGUGUGUGUGUGUGUGUGUGUGUAUUUGUUGUGAUUUGUUUUUAUGUUUUAGCAAUUUGGUCAGUUGCUUUAAAUUAGAGAUUUUGCCUGAUUGUUAUCUACAGAAUUCUAUGCAACUCCAUUACAUUAAGCUAAUAUCGCUUCAUUUUAUCUCUCAUCACAUUUUGUUUUUGUUUGUUUGUGCUGUGAAUUAUUGAGAUAAUGGGUUAAAUGUAUGUGCCUGUGUCCAUUUAUUUCAAUAAUAUCUUAUACUAUGACUCUAUAUUAUUAAUUGGGAAGAUUUUAGAAUACUUAACGUAUGUUUUCUAAUUAAGCAGUGACCCACUUAAUUUCUCAGAAGUACAUUUUGUUUUAUUGCUUUAAACUCUAUUUUGAUUGUUUUUAAUCUGAUCAUACAGACUUUUAUUUUGGCUGAUAUUUUCGUUACUUUUUUCUUAUUUUUAUCCUUUCUAUGUCUUUAUGAUUAAAUUGUGUGCCUUACAAGGAGGUUUUACUUUUUCCCUCAAUGGAUUUGGAAGAUAUAUGUUCUAUUUUUAUUUCUGUUGUUGGUUUCCUGAAAAUCUCAGCAUGCAUAUUUGACUUAAAUUCUAAAAUUAAUAAACACUUUCUUAAUUUCCUGAACAAUAAAAGGAAUUUCAAACAUAUUAUUGGUCAUCAUCACCUGCCUAUUAAAUAUGCUUUCCCACUAGGGCUGGGGCUAAUGGAAAAUACAUCUUAAAAAGUCUUCUGUGUAAAACAUGGGACUCAAAACAACACUAGGAAAAUAGCGUAGAUCAGAUAAUUCUCAUUAAAUCAGCUGUUUAUUAAAAAAAGCAAUGAGCAAGGAACAACAAAGUCUCCUUAGGAGGCAAAACAAAGUAUUAUUAAAAGUAUGUUUGAUGUUGCUGAAGAUUCUUUCAUAAACAUAUUAAAGUCAAUUAUAAUUCUGUUUUUAAUGACCUUAUUAGCUCAGAUGAUGUUUUAAUGAUUUGAGUUUAUGUAUUAUUUGAAGAAUCUCUAAAUAGCACUAUUAAGUGCUCUGAUAUGCAGUAAUAUUUAUAUUGAGAAGCAACUUUUUUAAUUGUUUGGGGAAAGACUUCUAUUUCUUAUGACAUGCUUCCUUUUCAUUGAGGAAUACCCAAGAUACCAAGUUUUCUUUCAGAAGUAAUUUGCAUUUUCCACCUUGAAGUUGUAUUUGCCAUUUUGUUUGUUGCCAUAGGAAAAUUCUUUUUUGAGAAUUUUUUUCUUAUAACGUUCUUCAUCUGAUUAAACAAACAAAAAACCCAUCUUUAUUUUUAGACUAAAAGCCUUUGAAUAAAAUAUUAUACAACUUUAAAUAAAUUUAAGAUGACAUUAUGACUUAUUAGGCCACAGUUAAAUAUGAGCUUCAUCUAUUAGUGAGUCAAUCAUAGGAUUUUCACACAUGGCUUUUGUUCACAGUAAGUUAUAUCAAUUAAGUUGCUUAGAAUGAACAUAUAGCUGAACUAAUAAGCAUGAAAUAUUUUCACUGAUUUAUAAGAAUCCAGAAAUUAUCAAUGAGUUUUCUUUUUCUAUUAUUUAAAAAAGUUUUUGCUUGGCAAAUCUUCCCCUCUAGGAGAUUAAAGUAUUUUUUGCUCAUUAAUCAAUGUAAGAACACCUUACUUUACAUUCAUUGAACUCUGAGGUUAUAGAACUGUGAACUUUUCGAUUUGUUCGGCUUGGGGAAUGUCAUAGUUCAUUCUGUGAGUGGAAGUUGCCUUUAACCACAUGAGAACAAAUAAGGGAAUAUUAAGGUUUUAACUCAAGGCAGCUGAUAUGCAAUGGCUGGGAUAAUGGCCAUUACCUAAAAGAAAGAAGGCAGCAAAUGGUUCCAGACAUUUAUAAUUAUGCAUCUGAAGUCAGAACACCUUUUCUUUUUAAACAUUUUCAAUUUGUGAUCUGCUUGAGGACUUGUACAUAGAUAGGCUCAAGAUAUUUUGAGUCACAUAUGUAAAUGAAAUGUUUUGAGCAAAGUUGUAACCCUGCCCACAAAAUAGCUUUGCUAGGGAACAGAUGUAACUUGGAGAAGUACCAAUUUUGUCAUUCUAGAUGAGAAAUCUUCUGGUGCCAUCAAUGGGAUGCAAUUUGGCUAGUCACACCUGGGUGACCAAUAUCCGGAGGCUCUACGUCAAGUCAUUGAACAUGGAUGGAUGCUCCAUUAAGUCAUUUAAAAUAAACUUCCUAGCAAGUGAUCUCUAGCAUCUCAAUUUAACUGUAUCCUUUGGAGAUUUAAGGAAAACUGACAAAGCUAAAAAUACCUCUGCUAGGGGAUCUAUUAGUAUUCUCCACAUUGCUACUGAAACUUGCUGCCUUUUCCUAGAAGCACAUGAAAGAAACCCUGGUCCAAGCGAACUGUCUCCUUCACCAAAGCCACCUUGGAGAGAGCCCACACGGAGACUGGAGAUGUAGACUAUUAAGAGCACUCAGCCACAGAGUCACUUUGGUUGUGUCACUUAACCUCUGUGCUCUUCUAAGCUCCAUUCCUGGCUUGUGUUGCAGGGAUGUUUUGAGGAUAUGUUGAUGUGUGUGACUCCUUCUCUGUGUGUUGCUAUUAAAGACAUUAAGAACUGAGCUGAGUAACAAACUUUCUAGAAAUGAAUGAAGAAAACAUAGCAAAAUUAUACCUAUUUUUUUAAAUUGAAGUACAAAGAAACUGUAGCUAUAAUUAUCUUUCUUGACACUAACAGUACAUGAUUCCUAAAUGCUAUUGCUCACCUCAAGUCAAUGUCACUUUGUAUUAAUGGAUUUAGUGUCAUGUAUGGUCUUGUUUUUUGAGGUCGUCUGAUGAAAUCAGAAUGAUUUCACUUAAGGCAAGGCAUAUUAAAAUACAAAUUCGUAAAGAUAAUACCUUGAUGUUUAUGUCUAUGCCAAACUUGCUCUGCUGAGUUCCUGGUGGAAUGAAAAGACUGUCUUUUUUUAAUUGUGAUUUGUUUAUGACUAACAGCAUGGAUUUGAGACAGUUAUGAAAAUGCCAUGGUAUCAUUCUGUAAAUAACUUUGUCUAUGUAAUUGUAGUGUAUACUUAUUAUUGACAACUUGAAGAAAGUACAUAAAGUACAAAAUAAAAGUUACCCAUAUUCUUAUCAGCCAGAUCUAACUAAUUUUACCAUUUUCAUAUCUCUGUGCAUACUCUUAAUAAAAAAUGGUAUAAUACAUUUAAGCAGA